ACUUGCGUUAAGAAGCAGUGAAUAAGCGGUAGGUUGACAGAGCUACCGUCUUCCUGUUUUUUUCCUCCAAUUUUCCGGCAGUUACUCCCAGUCAUGCCCGAGCCCUCAAAGUCCGCUCCUGCCCCGAAGAAAGGCUCCAAGAAGGCAGUGACAAAGGCCCAGAAGAAGGACGGCAAGAAGCGCAAGCGCAGCCGCAAGGAGAGCUACUCCGUGUACGUGUACAAGGUGCUGAAGCAGGUCCACCCCGACACCGGUAUCUCGUCCAAGGCCAUGGGCAUCAUGAACUCCUUCGUCAAUGACAUCUUCGAGCGCAUCGCCGGCGAGGCUUCCCGCCUGGCGCAUUACAACAAGCGCUCGACCAUCACCUCCAGGGAGAUCCAGACGGCCGUGCGCCUGCUGCUGCCAGGGGAGCUGGCCAAGCACGCGGUGUCGGAGGGCACCAAGGCCGUCACCAAGUACACCAGUUCCAAGUGAGCCCGCCCACCGCGGAACGUUCGGUCAGUCUCGGCCCACACCCCAAAGGCUCUUUUCAGAGCCACUCA